UAGCCUGAGUGACAGAGGAAGACUCCGUCUCAAAAAAUAAUAAUAAUAAUAAUCCUGGACUCUAGCUGAGUAUUAGGAUAAAAUUUUAAAAAUAUUACUGCCUUCACAUACAGAUGAACUCAAAAGAAGAGGUUAAAAUGCAGUUAUUACAUUUAGUUGGUUCUUUCCUCCAAUAGGAGAGUAUUCAGGAAGAUUGCCAAAAAACUUGGUAAUUGAGCUUUCCAAAGGGGGUUCAGGUGAUCCUCAGUGACAGUUCAGGCUGUGCCAGGUAUGCACACUGGAGCCACGUCAGACCCCAGUCUUAAUAUGUUUCUCUAAGGUGACCUUCCAAACAGUGUUCUACGUGCUUGGUUUGGAGCCAAGUUGGUUUUGUGUAGUGCUCUAGCCACAAAUGGUUUAACAUGUUCUAUUUACAAACGUGUAGCCAGAUAGUAUGGGUGUCAUCAAAAGAAUGAUUUGCCAGUUCUACCUUGUUAUCAUGGGAAUUUAUUUUGGGAAUAAAGAAACUGAAUGUUUAGUCAGGGCCUUUAUACAAAGCAAAGUGAAAUCAUAUUGGAAAGAGAACAAAGACAUAUGUGAAAUGGAAUAUUAAGAAGAGUCAUCUUAAAAGAAAUCCAGUUGGACCAAGUGUUUGAAGACCUGUGGCAUCCCCAGCACAGAAGCUCCACUAAGGCUUUAAAUUGUUGGGAUUUCCACUCGGGCUGGAGCACUGGCUCCCCCGUGGUCUAAGCUGCCACUAUCACUGUGUCUUUAGUGUAGGAAUUUUUAACCUGGAGUCCACAGGUUCCCAAGUGGUCCACGAAUAGAAUUCAGGGAGUCCAUGAACUUAGACAAAUAUUACAUCUUAAUUUUCAUUGACCUCUAACUAAAACAUGGCAUUUUUCUCAGUUAUGAAGGUAGGCAACAAACCACUGUAGUACUUAACAGUGCUGGUGACUUUAUCAUCAUGUUCAAAAGAGGUUGGCCUGUGAUUUUCCUCUCUUUAAACGUCCUUGUGAGGUCUUGGUAUCAAGGUUAUGCUGGCCUCAAACAGGUUGAGGAAUUUUAUUCUCUGGCAGAAUUUGUGAACAGGUGGUGUUACUUCUUCUUUAAAUACUUAGUAGAAUACUUUAGUGAAGCCCUUUGGGGCCUGGAAUUUCUUUAUGGGAGAGUUUUCAAAUGUAGAUUUAAUUUACUUAAUAGAUACAUGAUUGUUCAGAUCUUCUCUUUCUUCUUGUAUUUGUUUUGACAAGUUUCUUCUUCCUAGAUAUUUGCCCGUUUCAUCUCUUUUCAAAAUAAUGAGUGAAAGUUGCUCAAAAUAUCCUCUUGUCUUUAUAAUGUCUGUAGAAUCUAUAACAGUGUCUUCUUUUUCAUUCUUGAUAUUAGUUAGGUAAAAAUUGUAAACAUUAACAAAACUCAGGGUCCUUAAGGGUUUAGGGAAAUGGUCACUAUUGAUAGGAGUCCAAGUUAUACAACUUUUCUAGAAAACAGUGUAUAUCAAACAUAAAAUGUUAGUAUAUUUCAUCCAACAACCCCUUUUAAGGAAUUUGCCAUAAGUAAAUAAUCUCACAGAAAUAUUCAACACAGGAUUACCUAUAAUAGCAAAAAAUAUUGAAAAAAAUCAAUAGGGGACAAGGAAGUAAUUAAAUUCACUAGAAUGCCCUCAUGUUAUAAAACAUAGCAUAUUGACAUGGAAAAGUGCAAGGGACAUAUCGUUAGUUACAAAAAGCAGGUUGCAGAAGAGCAUAUACAGUGUAGGCUCUUCUGUGUUGAAACAUAUACAUCAAUAUAAAUGAAUAUGUACAUAGAGAAUGGUUUGGAACCAUGGUUAUCAAAAUUCUAACAGCAGUUAUCUAUGAGUGGUAGGAUGUUGGGUAGUAGUUAUUUUCUUUUUGCUCUUCUGUAUUGUUUAAGAUGUUUGCAUGAGCAUGCAUCAUUCCUACAAAAAUAGCAAAACUUUCUAAAGAUCUUAGCAGUUUGCAAGAUGAGAGGGUGGUAGGGGAGGAGAGUGUCAAAGCAUUUUUGUUGCCUCCUGAGGAACAGUCAGGGAAGGAGAGUUUGGAGCUGUAAGAAAGAAGGGGUAAUCGGCUGAGUAAAGCCCUUAGAAAGAUAGGAGGGCCUGUACUCAGACACAGAAGUUACCCUUAAAGGGACAGGACAAUAUUUCUUUCCAGAAAGGAGGAAAAGAUGAUUGAAGAUAUGGAGAAGUUCAGAGCUGGAGAGAAGGGAAAAUUAGAGUGUUCAUAAGCCACGGCUUCUAAUUUCUUGGUGAAAUCAGAGGUAAGACCAUUUGCCAGGAGGUGGGGGUGGGAAUCAGAGUAGAACAGGGGUCUUGAGGAAAGUGAUAAGAGUCUCCAAUAGAACUGACAGCAGGAAAGGGAUUUGAUGGGGUGUGGGCAGCUGAGUUGAUCAGAGGCCUUACUGGAACUAUAAGCCCGCAUUUUUAGGGAGCCCAACAGAGCAUGAUUGGUAUGGAGUUAGAGGGUGGCCCAGCAGGCUUCACAGAGCUUCAGAGGAUGAGAGAAUUCAGGAUACUGAUAAGGGCAAUUUAAAUGAUUGGCUUUAGAAUCCAAAUCCUUGGGAGAAGAGUGAAUUAGAGAUAGUGCCAAGGACUGGAUAAUUAAUUAAUUAGUUGGAAUAUGGGUAUCCAAGAGGCCAAAGGAUAGGAGUUUAUGGCCAAAGUGGGGUUUCAGAGUUUGACAUUUUAUAGGAAUUCUGGGCAACCUGGAGUUUAAUAGGUAGCCAUGGAAGUAAAGGAACGAUCAUAGAAUGUGGGUAGGUCAGAGGGUUGUGUUGCUGGAAGUUUCAGUGUUCUUCCUCAUGGAUGAGAGCAUUUCCCAGGGAGGUGACAGGAAUUCUUUUGGAGAAGAAGAUUUUGAGGCAGGUAGAGAUUGUCUUCAAGGAUGGAAAGAAAGUUGACUCCUCAGGGAAGGCUUGAUGAAGAGACCUAGUAGUGUCGUGGUGUGAGCUACUGUGGGGUAGCAGGAAGUUUGCUGACCCUCUCUCCCAAGGCUGGGAACCUGGACCCUGGCAGAAGUCUCUCUUCGAGGCUGAAGAGCAAAACCAGGUUUGCAGUACCAGAGACUGGCAGGAAAAAUGAUCUGGAAACGAAGAAGAAUGCUCUGCAGAAGCUUCUUAGCAAAGGGACAAGGGGUCUGGGGUACAGGUGAGCAGGAAAAAAGAUGUGAGAAAGUAGGUUCUGAAGAGAGACAGACUAGUGCUAGGAAGGGCUGAUCUGCAAAGGGGUGGAGAUUUAUAUGCAGGUUUUCCAAAGGAAAUGCCAAAUGGUAUAUUUCUUUUAAUCACAAAGUAGUGUCUGCUUACUACAGAGAGAACUGAAACUACAGCCAAGCAAACAGCAAAAACAAGUAAACAAAAGAAGCGUAAGAACUACCCACAAUCUCAGGGUCCUGGAGCUUUUCCAGUUGACAUGUUCCUCCCCUCCAUUUCCCACUGCCACAGCUUCAGGUCAAGGCCACAAAGGCCACAUUGCUUUUAGAAUGAGCUUGUGCUCUGGUUCCCAAGUGUCUCUAACUGAGCCCCCAGGGCUGCCUGAACCCCACCCUUCACGUCCUACUUGGGCUGCCAAAGUCAUCUUCCCAAAACAUGACUUUUCCUCAGUCACUUUUCUUAUUAGAUUUUAUCAUAUUCCACAUCCCUUCCCUGGCCCUCAAGGGUGCCUGUAACCUAGAACCAUCUUACCUUUCCACCCUUGUUUCCAAACCUUCCGCUUUACUUAGACAUGCCUUCCCAUUUCCCUCCCGACCCACUUCCCUCACAGCCUCACAUCUGGGUCUCUGUCCCCUCACUAGGAUGUCUGCCCUAUCACAAUGACCAGUCCCAUCCAGAUUAUGCCAGUUGUCGAGGUCCCAUACCCUACUUUAGCCCAUAGUGAUUUUUGCCCUUCCAGUUACUCAUCUGAUCACCCCUUUUAGGAUUUACAUUAGUUCUGUUCCAGUAAAGGCUUAGGUAGGAAGCACAGGAUGUAGAGCUGAGUUGAACCUAUUCCCCUGAUCUUACUAAUGAGGUGCCUGAUAUUCAGAGAGACCAAGGGACAUCCCCAAAGUCAACCAGCAAUCCAUUAGAGCUGAGCCUAGUACCUUGAUUCUCAGACAUGAAUGCUACUUGUUGAAUUGAAAAUUGCAUUCAUAAUACAUCUCUUCAUAGAUUCCUGGCCAGGAAGCCCCAGAGACCAAAACAGUGGUUAUCAAUAUUUAGAAUAUAUCAGAUUUACCUGGGGAGCUUUAUCAAAAUCCACACUCCUAAGCCCAAUAGGGGGAAACUCUGAUGUGGUAGGUUUAGGGUAAGACCUGAGUAUUUCCAAGAAAACCUCCCUGGAUGAUCCUGACACAGGGAGCUUUCAGAUCAUCCUUUGAGAAAAUCUGCUUUAGAGCUCAUUCUUUGGUUCGGCUUUCUCUUUUGAGCUCACUGAUAUCAUCCCUGUGGACACUGAAGCUUUUCUGAAGCUUUCUCAUCUCAGGAAUUGGUUUGGGUUACUCUACAAUCAGAUUUCCAUCCAGGAUGUCACGGCAGUGGCUCAGUACUGCAGCCUGUGUACCUUCUCAGCCAAACUGGCCUGGGCCCAAGCUUGGGCCAGGUUAUUUUUCAAAGUACUCUUGGGCAUACUGUGACACAAUAUUGAGCAUAGUAGAAUUCUUGUGGGAAACGCUCCGUUUGUCAAGGUGUUUGUGAGCACCUUCUGAAGUGUGGAUGCCUAGCCUCUGUGGCCUGCCAACUGUCUGCACCACAGGUUAACCAAACCCAAACUGUCUGCACCCAAGUAAACCCAAUCCAAACAUGAGCCUUGAGCUUGCCAAACCCCAGCACAUGGAGACCUGGGCCAGGAUUAGGAGGUAGAGAGGCAGUUUGUAUAGUGAUGAGGGCAAGGCUCUGGGGCACACUGCCUGGGUUUGUAUCCCAGUUCCACGGUUUCUAGCUGUGUGACCUUUAACAUGUUUCCUCAUCUAUAAAACAAGAACUCAAACUAUAAAAAUAAUUAUAUUCUACAAAAUAAAAAUAAUUCCUAGCUCCCAGGAUGGUUAUAAGGAUAACAAAUCUAUGCAUGUGAAGCGCUUAAAACAGUGUUUGGCGCAUAGUAAGUGUUCAAUAAGGGCUUGCUAUUGUUAAAAUUAUUUCUUGAAAACUGGGGUGAAAUACUUAGACUGCAAAGAGAUAACUCAGUAUGCGUCUGUGCAGUUAUCAGUCUAAAAGUUAUCAAUUAUCUCCUGGUUGCAUGCAUGAGCAUAGAUCCGAAGAAUGACAAGCGAUAUAGUAAUAGCUCCUCCAAAUGCUGCCUGGACCUCUGAAGACAAUUUAAAAAUGCUAGGUAUUUCCCAGCAAUAAGGUCAAGCCUUGCAUAAUUUAAGAAAUAUACAGCAAUUCCACAUUUUGGUGCUUUGAUAAGGUGGCAGUUACAUAACAGGCUGCAACCACGCAGAUGAGCAGAGCCAAAGGUGGGGGAGAGGGUGUUCUGAAAAGAUGUGUGAGUGUUGGAGUGAAGGCUGUGCGAGAUGAAAGACAUGGCAGCAGUUACAGUCUUCAUAAAGUUUGGGUCUGAAGGAUCCACGCAUGCCCUGUGACAUUAUAAAUGGCCUGACAGCAGGAAAAACAUCUCCUGACAUUUACUGUCAGGCUAACACCAAUGGGAGGAAUGAAAGUUUGCCUUAUAUUUGUCAUAUUACCAAUGUUUUCUUAUUCCUUGAUAAUGUUUUUAAGCUAAAAGUAAGAUUGCAUCAGUCUCUAAGGUGACACAAAGCUGAAUUUGUCUCUAGAAUUUAUAUGUUUUAUCAAACUUUUGCAAAAGACUCAACUUAGAGUGUUGCCAAAGCAUCACCUUCCUGUAUCACGUUGCCAAGUUAACUUUUCUUGAUGCUCCGACUUAGUGGUGCCAUUCUCCAAAUUCCAAGUACAGGAGAGCCCUAGAAGGGUGUCAGAAAGCAGGUUGCAGUAGCUUACUUCUGUUUUUGGGUAGGAGAUGCUGGUCCGUGAGCACUCAGCAAGUGAUCCUGUGUGCUAACCACUAAAAUACUUAGACCACCCUGUUUGAGUUGUAUGAUAUCUCUUUAAAAGGGAACUGACUGGUUUACAUAGAUUGCGUAGUAUUUAUCAUAACAUAAUGCUCAGACUUUUAGAGACCAGAAAGCCAGUUUGUUUGGGGGACCAUCUUUAGGCCUAGCAUCAUCCUCAUCUCCUAGAAGUGGCCAGAAUAGCUUGGUUGUUGCCCAACCUUUUUGGAUAUGAUGCUGUAGCUGGGGGCCUUUAGAUCCAGGGGUAAGGAGAGUGCUAAAGGGCACUGCCACCAGCCAGGGCAGGCUGAAAGCUUUGGCUCUGCCUCAGCACUUGUUAGCCUACCAUUUUCCUUAGCAAGAAGCUGCUGUGGAAUGAGUUCCUGGGAGUGGAUGAGGCCCAGGUAAGCCUUGUUGGAUUGAAAUGUAUAAUCUUACCUCUGGGUCUUUUAAAAUAAAUCAAAUUUUAAUAUUUACAAAUGAUAACAGAAUUUGGAAUGAAGAUUUUCUUUUUAUUGCUGCCUGUCCAAGCACCAUGGGAGAUCAGAAUGUUAGCUUGAUGGCUGAGUAGCAGGCAGUAAGCAGGGAGGCCUUAGCUAGCUGUAACUUUUAUUUAUUCAUGUACUCCCUCCUCAAUACAGGACGUGGACCACACUGUGCCGUAGAGGGAGGACGUUGACAUAACACGAUCUGACCUCAAGCCCUUAUAUAUAAGGCAUUAAUUUGGAUAUCAAACUGUUUGAAAUUUUUUGUAAUAAAGUUUUUUAAAACUUAGCACAUUUGAGGAUAAGAAGGAGAUCUUGGAAAAUAAAAAUAUCACUAACUAAACAAUUAUAAAAUGUAAUAGAAGGGCUAGAAAAUGAAAUCGGCGGUUUCCAAAAGGUAGAAUGAAAAGAUGAAGAGACAGAAAAUAGGGGAGAAACAACAAAUAAAACUUUAAAUGGCACAUCCAGGAGGUUCAAUAUCUGGCUAAUAGGAGUUCCAGGAGAACACAGAAAAGAGAGAAAAGGAAAUUAUCAAAGAAAUAAUGUGAGAGAAUUUUCAGAACUGAAGGUCAAGACACUCUAUUUUGAAAGAUGUUUUCAAUCUAGAGGCCAAUACAAUGAAUGGAAAAAAUUAGCCACACCUAGGCACAUUAUAAUCGACAUCCCAAAUGCCAGAAAUAAUCAUAAAAGCUUUUGGAGGGGGAAAACUUGUCCCAAACAAACUGAUGAAAAUCUGAAUGCUAUCAGGUUUUUAAACAUCAAUACUGAAAGCUAGAAGACAGAAUAAAGUCAGUAAAAUUUGGAGGGUAAGUUAUUUUCCGUUUAGAAUUUUAUAUACAGUUGAACUUUCAAUCAAGUGUAAAGACAGAACAAAGACAUUUAAAAAUCUGCAAGGACUGAAAAUUUUGCUUCCUGCGGAUUUUUUUCUAGGAAACAACCAGAAUAAGUACUUCAUCAAAAUGAGGAAAUAAAUAAAAAACAGAGAAACAGAACCCAGGAGCCAGAAAACCAACACAGGAAAACAGCCAUGAGAAGCCCAGUGGUGUAGGCCCAGCUACUUGGGAAUUCCCAAAUGAUCUGAUAUAACCGACCAUUUGGAAAAUCACACAUGUGCGGAUGCAUGCACACUCAACGUAUGCGCGCACACCCACACAGAGUUAAGGCAGGAUAUUUGGAAAAAUUUGAAUAUAGAUGCAUAGAAUAUUAAGCAAAUGAAAUAAAGAGGGAAUGUUAACUGUAAGGGAGUUGUACAAGGGAAAAUAAAACAAAACUUAGCUUUUUAAUGAACAGUUCUUACAAUAUGUAAGGGAAGGGAAAAUGUGGUGGUGCAAAAGAGCUAAAAUGUAAACAGUUAAACAGGAAAUUAAUAGUUGAAGGAUAAAAUAGAGAAAUCAAGAAAUGACAAUAUUAGUAUAUUUGGUUAAAAAAAGCUAAAAGCUUUGAAAGUGUUUGCCUCAAAGUAGUGGGUUUUAAAAUUUUUUUUCAGCAAUUUGAUUUAAACCAUGUGAUUUUGUUUGUUUUGAUAAAAAAGUAAAAGUUAAAAGUUUGACUGUGAAUAGAAAACUCAAACCAGUAUCAUCCAAGAAGCUUUUGCCACCACAGGCGUCGCCAGCAUGGUGGGUAGAGCACAGAGUCUCCAUCAGAUCCAGGCUCCGUGCUCUGAGGCUCCUCCUCACAGGAUGUCCUCCCUGUCUGUUGGCAGGUAACUGGGCUAUCUCCUGCCAGAGCCAUACCAAGUUUCAGAUGAGGUUAUAAGGCUGAGCGGGAGUGUAUACCUAAUAACAGGAAGGGAGGAAAGAGGAAGGAAGGAGAAAAUUUCCUUCAUAGAUGGAUUUAGAAAACGGUUUUGCCACCUUGUUAUUGAGACAACUCCAAGGAAAUUCUAUCUGAAAUCCACUCACCAGCGGAAUAUGGCAUCAAAUGACAAUUCUACUUCACUGUCUGAAGCUUGCCUAGUAUGACACAAGAGUAUAUCUCUAGGCCAGCCCCAGGGGUAGAGUUAACCAGUGGGCACACUAGGCUCUCCCAUGCCUACCCUGUUCCAUGCUGGGGUUAGGAUAUGGUUCUAGGCUGACUUGAUCCAGUAAUCAGUCUAGAGAACAGAGAAUGAACCAGAUUUCCUUCCAUCCCUACCCGUUACCCAGGGAGUGACCUUUCCAUACAUCACCACCGCUGACCUACAGUACCUUAUAUAUCUGGGAUCUACCCCAAACCAGAUUAAUCCAUGUCUGGGCUCACUGUGUGUCUGGUUAUAAUUGGACCACCCAGACCACAGUGAUAUUCAAGCAGCCAUUCACUUCUCUGUACCCUACUUCUGUUGACCAGCACUGGCUGAAAGCAGUGGUUGUGAAGGAAAGGGCCCUUCUACUCCUACGCACAGGUGUGCAGGGCACCAGGCCAGCUGCAAGCGAGGACACAGCUGUUUGUGGAGACUGUGUGCAUUAAAACCCAGACUGUCCUCUUUUACUGCAGGCUUAGAGUGCCGUUUUAUAGUGGAAACUGUUGUACUGAAUUCCUAGUAGGGAAGGACCCAUUUGCACUUAAAAUUAGUUUUCAUUUAACCUGUUAAUGGAAGCAUUUUUUAAAAAGAAUAUCUUUCAUUUUUCAGAUAGUGAGUCACUUUCUUAAAAUGUGUUUGUUUGUUUAUUAUAGAAGCAGUACAUGCUUGUAACAGGUUGAAACAAUAAAAAAUUUUUAAAAAAGGAUUGCCAUCCCUCACCCUAAUUCUAUCCAUAGAGAAUAAGGAUGAUGUACUGGUCCAUAGAGAAUAAGGAUGGUGUACGUGUAUAUCUGUCUGUACAGCUUUGUACAACAUAUAUAUGUGUGUGUACAUACAUGUACAUACAUGUACACACAUAUAUAUGUGCUUAUGUACUUUACAACAGCUAUAACAAUACAUAUAUAAUCAUUUAAUAAAAAUGAGAUCAAUACAACUUUUGUUUCUGUUGACAUACAUUGUAAACAUCUUUUAAUAUCAGAACCUACAGAUCGGCCACAUUUUCAGGAAUAUUCUUUAUAUGGAUGCACCUUAAUUCAUCUAUGCAUCUCCCUACUGAUGAACACUUAGGUUCCCCAGACUUUUGAUAAUUAGUAUCAGUGCUGCAUUAACACCUUUAACUCUGAAGUCAGACAGAGUUAGUUCAGGUUCUAGAUACUCAAUUACUUACUUUAGCAAGUUAUUUAAACUCUCUGUGCCUCAAUUUCCUGAUUUGUUAAAUGGGAAUAAAAUUGUUCUCACAGUGUUCCUAUUAAAAAAGGCUAAAUGAAGGAAUACAUAUAAAGGCACCUAACAUUAUAAUAAUGAUAGCUAACAUUUAUUGACUACUUACUAUCAGCCAGGUACUGUGUGUAAACAAAUACCAACUGUUUUAUGCUUUAGUCUUAUAACAUAUUUUUUUAAUACCUGUAAAGGCAUCAUCACCAUUAAAAUGGCAUUAGCUAUUUCUAUGCAUUUACUCCUCCAAUAAAUUUUAAAAUCAACUUUCCACCUACCUCUCAUCAAUAUGACAAGUUUUUUUUUUUAAUCCAGUUGGAAUUCUAAAGGGUAUCUCCACUUCUGAAGGUUGCCAGAGUAGAAAGACCCUUAAGCUUGAGUCAGAGAGAACUGAGUGUUCUUAUGGUGUCCCUCCAAAGCCACGUGACCAUAAGCAGUUCAUUUAAACUCUCUGAGCAAUUGCACUUUCCCUACCUGUAAAUGGGAGGGUCAAUCCUUACAGAAGUGGGGGGGAUAGUAUAAGAAAGCUGGAACGAUGUCUGACAAUAAAUACUUAAUAAGUGUGCUUGCUUCUGAGGCAAGUGUUUUUAAUUUAUCUUCUGGUCCUUUGUCUUCAGCACCAUUUUCAGUGGCAGCUCUAAGGUGAUCUUUAGGGAAAAGAGUUUGAGAGUGAGAGCAGCGGUGAACAUGCAGGAUGAAGUUUAAGGCCCCCACUUCCUCUGCAAGGCAAGCUGAACAUUUACAACCAGUGAAGAUUAGCCAAGAGGGAGGAAAGGGAAUUGGGACAAACAUAGACUGUUCCAUUGUGCAGGCAUGUGCCACCAACCGUGGAGUGGACUUCCUGCUGCAGGACACAGCUGACCUUUGGAGAGUCACUGUCUGAGUGAGGCUGCCCUUUAGCAGGACAGAACACAGCUGUUGUUUGGAUGUCAGAGGCUAGUUAAUAACUGUGUUUGGCAAUCAGCUUGGGAUGUUAACAGCUUCUAGGUUUAAGGAAGGCCAGAAGAAUAGUAUGAAGGAAAUCUUUGUGUUACCAACAGGUUCUUUGGUAAUCUUUCUUUGAACAAAAAUUAACACUUCACAGCAGCUUUAAAAAGUAUUAAGAGAACUCAUAAAAGUCAGAGCAGAUGUGCUGGAGAUCACACUUCCAGAGCUCUCUGGGGAACUAUUUCUGGACUAACAAGUCCAACAAAUGUGUUAAUUCAGGUUGAGAUUUCUAAUGCAAAUAUUGACUCAAUCUCAACCUUUGCAGUUAAUUCUCCAACUCGAAUGUGUCCUUUCAGGAUACCUUGCCUGUUUUCUUUCUUUAUGCCUAAUCAUUUGCCUACCCUUCAUUUUGAAGGUGGUUAGCAGGUGGUUGUUUAGUGGUCAGUUCUACAUUCUUUCUCUAGGUCUCGAUAAUGUUUAGAGGAAUAAGUAUAAAUAUUCCUUGAUUUUCUUAGUGGUAUAAUUGCGGAAAAGGAGGAAGAAGAGAUAGCCAGGGCGGUAUAGACCAGUAUAAAUGAUUCUCAGUCUUAGAGCAGAUUACAGAAAAGUAACUUCUUGCACACUAUUCAGUAUUAAAGAAAAAAUGGGUGACAGAUUGUUUUGUUGAUUUUUCCCCCCAGCCCACAUGAUAUUUUUAAUUACUCUUAAUUUUUAAAUGUGUUUUGAAGUUUGUAUGAAUUGGUAUGCAAACUGCUACGUGGCUAACCAUUAGUAUAAAAUAAAAAGUUUUGACUAAAAGAUAAUGUAAAGGUAAUGUAAACUUAAUGUAAAGUUCACCUUCAUACUUGAAGGAUAUUUUCACUGGAUAUAGAAUUCUGGGAUGAAGUUCUGUUUUGUUUUAAGAGAAAAGAUCUCACGGUGUCACCCAGGCUGGAGUAUAUAGUAGCACAAUCGUAGCUCACUGCAGCCUUGAACUCCUGGGCUCAAGUGAUUCACCUGCCUCAGCCUCUCGAGUAGCUCGGACUACAGGCACACACCACCUUAUCCAGCUAACUUUAAAAAAAGUUAUUUUUUUUUUUUGUAGAGACGAGAGUCUCGCUAGAGUCUCGCUAUAUUGCCCAGGCCGAUCUCAAACUCUUAGCCUCAAGCAAUUCUCCCACCUCCGCCUCCCAAAGCACUGGGAUUACAGGCGUGAACCACCAGGCCCAGCCAAGUUUUUUUUUCCAAAUGCUGUUAUAACGAUCUCCUGGCAUCCUUGGUUUCUGAUUCAAAGUGAGUGGUCACUGGAAUUAUUGUUACUUUUAUGUAAUGUAUAAUUUUCCUUUGGCUACUUUCAAGAUUUUCUACUCUUUAUCUUUGGCUUUCUUUAUGUUUAUCUUGCUUAGACUUUAUUGAACUUCUUAAAUCUGUAAAUUUAAAGACUUUGCAGCCAUUAAAAAAAUAUGUUUUUUCUGUCCCAUUCUCUCUCUCUUUGCCUUCUGGGACUAUGGUUAAACCUAUGGUAGACCUUUCAAUGUUGUCCUACAGGUCUGAGGCUCUGUUCAUUUAUUUUCAAUCUUUUUUCCUUUCUGUUCUUCAGAUUGGAUAAUUUCUAUGAAUCUAUCUUCAAGUUCACUGACCUUUUCUGUUAUCACUAUUCUGUUAAGCUCAUCCAGUGAUUUUUAAAAUUUUUCACAUAUUAUAUUUUAAAUUCUAGAACUUUCAGUUGGUUCUCUCUUAUACUUUCUCUGCCAAGGUUUCCUAUAUAUUUCAUAUAUUGCUUUAUGCCAUUGAGCACAAUUAUAAUAGCUAUUUUAAAAAAUCUUAUCUGCUAAUUGCACCGUCUAGGUUAUCUUGGAUUCUCUAUUGACUGUCUUUUUUCUUGAGGAUGGGUUGCAUUUUCCUAUUUAUUUGUAUGUUAAAUAAUUUUGGAUUGUAUUUUGGACAUUGUGCAUAUUACAUUGUGGAGACUCUGGAUUCUAUUAUAUUCCUCUGUACAGGUUUUCCGGGAAGUGAGGGGUCGUUGUUUAUUAUUGUUUCUUUUGUUUUUUGCCAUUGCCAACAUUCAGCUUGGUUGAGCUAAAACCACAAACUCUGUCUCUGAAUCGAGGCACUACCUCAAUUCUCGGCUUAGUUAUUUUAUCCUUAGCUAGGUUGCUUAGCGUCUGCCCCAUGCAUGCAUAGUUCAGUGGUCAGCCAAAGAUUUGGGCAGUUUUUACAUAGAAUUUGGGGCUCUCCCUUUCUGGCUCUGUACUUUCUGGAUUCUCCCCUUUCACUUUGUAGUGGCUGUGAUUGUCCCAAAGUCUGUCACCCAAGCACUACAUGCUGUCUAUUGGAGUUUUAGCCAUGCAGCAUGGCACUGGUGGCAGCCUGACACCAGGCUGAAAGCCAUAAAACUGAAAAACAUAUCUAGAUCUUUUUCCAUUUUCCAAGUGUCAUUCUCCCCGCUCUGAAAUCUGCUUACUGUCUAUCUUUUUACAGUGCUUCCAGGUAGUUAUUUUUUAUAUUUUGUUAAUAGUUUAUAGUUUUCUCCAGGAGAAUCAGUCUAGGAUGGAAAACCUAGUCUAUGGUAGAGGAAAAAUAAUCAAAACAGUAGUUUCCUAUAGAGAAGUAAGAGUUUUUACCCAGGUAUAUAUAUUUGUCAAGACUCAGUGAAUGUACACUUAAGAUUUGGGCACUUCACUGAAUGUAAAUUUCACCUCAAAAAAAACUAAUAGUGAACUGUAGUUAAUGACAGGCGUAUGUUUGAACAUUUACAAAAUAAAAUAUUGAGAAGAAAAAGUGAAGUAAAAUUGUACUUUUUGAUUCCAUGUACACAGAAUUCCUGAAAUGCAGUUGGUUGAGGCUUCAUUGGGAUCUGCUUUUAUAAACAGACAAGAAAAAUGUGUUAUGAACACAUUUGUUCUCAGUUUCUUGAGCGCUCCUAUAAACAAAGGGCUGUGGAAUAAUCAAUCAGUAAGAAUCAGAUGUUUUCCCUGCCUUCUGGAAACUUGCAGCCUAACGAAGGAUAUGAUACAAACAUACAAAUGAUUGAAUGCAGAAUUUGAUACAUCCUCUAAGAGAGGUACAGACGUGCUGGGGUGUUGUUCAGUAGAAUAAGCGCAUAUUAGGUUUGAGGAGCCACGGAGGCUGCAUGAAAGAGGGGUAUCUUAAAACAGCAGGACAGAGGGCAUCACCAAGGGGGCGGAAGGAUAUCCAAGGUGCAGGAGUCUGUGUAGAUGUUUAGAGUGAUGUGAAAAAGAGCUAGAAAGGUAGGACCAGGGCCUUGAAAACCAAUUUUGGGUUUUAUUCAAUAGAUAGGUAGGAGACAUCAUGUCUUUCAGUGAGGUGGGAAGUGAAUGCUUUAACAUUGUGUUAUUUUGUUAUUUUUAAUUGUUUUUGAGACAGAGUCUUGCUUUGUUGCCCAGGCUGGAGUGCAGUGGUGUGAUCACAGCUUACUGUAACUUUGACCUCCCGGGCUCAAGGGUUCUUCCCACCUCAGCACCCCCUGAGUAGCUGGAACUACAGUCACAUACCACCACACCUAGCUAAUUUUAAAAUUUCCUGUAGAGGCAGAGCCUCACUUUGUUUCCCAGGCUGGUCUUGAACUCCUGGGCUCAAGCAAUCCUCCCACCUCGACCUCCCCAAGUGUUGGGAUUACAGGCGUGAGUCACCAUGCCUGGCCAACAUUCAGUUAUUCGUGUGAUACUUAGAAAUGCAGGACUUUCAGGUGGGACCCUGCCCCCUCAGCCUCCUCUCCCCUUCACUGUGAGGCUUUAUUUCAGACACAUCCUCUUGGUAGAGGGCCCAGGCUGGCACUUUAAUUUGAAGGAGUUAGACUAGAGGCUCUCCACAGUUCUUUCAGCUCAGCAUUCUAUGAUCUGAUGGCUGCUUGAAAGAGUUGUUUCUUGCACAGAUUAAAUAUUUCCUCUUGCAGUAUUAUUUUGCUCUGUUAGCCAACUCUUCUUCAUAAAGUCUGGAUUGUACUGUAAGAUAUACAGUAAUACAGAUUCGAUAUUCAGAGUGUCAGAACUCAUGAGCUGUUGCUGUGUGGUGAUGUUGUUUUUCACAGCUGUAACAUUUUAAGCUAUUGAACUUUCACGUUAUGAAAAAAAUGACUGUGCUGUUAAGCUAGAUGGGGGCUAUAGGGGGAAGCUUACCAAGUUUCUCAUGAAGACCUAGUAGUUCUGCACAUGUCGCAGGUAAGUCUGGAUAAUCCCAAUUUAUUUUACUUAUUGAUUUUUUUCCCAAUUUAAAAUGAUACUCUUCACAGAAUGCUUACGUCAUUCUGCUAAUUUCCAAAUGCAAGUAGGAUGUUAAAAUUUUAUGGGACAGUAUAAUUUCAUUUCUUGAAAAGAAAAUCUCUUACUGUAUGAGUUUUUAGCCAUCUUUCUAUUAUCUCUGAUGUAGUAAGUGUGUUAAUCUUUGUCUCAGAAAUAAAAAUCCCAAACAAUGUAUUGAACCAUUGGGUGAGCGGUGAAAAGUUAACUUUUCAUCUCUAAACAUCCAGGCCUAGAUGGACAUCUGCUUGUGUGAAGAGUGAAGGCAGGAUGCUGGAAAAUUGUUAUUUUCAGACCACUAGGGUCAAGCAUCAGAAGUGAGAAAGGACUGAUAAGCUGAAAAAGUUGUACGAUAUGGGAAUGCAAACUUUUUGUGAGAAAAACAGAAAGAAAAGUAGCACAGAGCACUGCCAUUAGUAAGUUUGCCAUUGCCGUUGUGUGUGAUAACUGGCUUAGACUUAGUUCCGGAAAUCCAAGUGUGAUUAUUUUUGGAGUGCCGGUUAUACACUAGAGAGCUCUGUCAUAGAGAAAAUGUGUUUAUCUUUUAUUCACUUUUCAUCUUAUUAGGGAGAAACCAUGCCCUGACCUCAUAAAAAGCAUUUGAACACAAAGCCACAACUCUUCAAGUGCCUCGUAUAUUUGUCAUCUGAGAACUGGGCAAAGAUGGUCAAUAUUCACAUUUAUUGCCGGAAUGAGUCCAGAGUAAUUUCAGAAGCACCAGGGUGUUUUACAAAGAAGGUCUUCUGUCAGGGAACCCCAGAAUGAAAGAUCUCAGAUCAGAGCUGCUUCAAAGAGCCUCCCAGUGCAACGUCAGCUUAAAGAAGCAGAGGAGCCGCAGCAUCCUUAGCUCCUUCUUCUGCUGCUUCCGUGAUUACAAUGUGGAGGCCCCUCCACCCAGCAGCCCCAGUGUGCUUCCGCCACUGGUGGAGGAGAAUGGUGGGCUUCAGAAGGGUGACCAGAGGCAGGUCAUUCCCAUACCAAGUCCACCAGCUAAGUACCUUCUUCCAGAGGUGACGGUGCUUGACUAUGGAAAGAAAUGUGUGGUCAUUGAUUUAGAUGAAACAUUGGUGCACAGUUCGUUUAAGCCUAUUAGUAAUGCUGAUUUUAUUGUUCCGGUUGAAAUCGAUGGAACUAUACAUCAGGUGUAUGUGCUGAAGCGGCCACAUGUGGACGAGUUCCUCCAGAGGAUGGGGCAGCUUUUUGAAUGUGUGCUCUUUACUGCCAGCUUGGCCAAGUAUGCAGACCCUGUGGCUGACCUCCUAGACCGCUGGGGUGUGUUCCGGGCCCGGCUCUUCAGAGAAUCAUGUGUUUUUCAUCGUGGGAACUACGUGAAGGACCUGAGUCGCCUUGGGCGGGAGCUGAGCAAAGUGAUCAUUGUUGACAAUUCCCCUGCCUCAUACAUCUUCCAUCCUGAGAAUGCAGUGCCUGUGCAGUCCUGGUUCGAUGACAUGACGGACACGGAGCUGCUGGACCUCAUCCCCUUCUUUGAGGGCCUGAGCCGGGAGGACGACGUGUACAGCAUGCUGCACAGACUCUGCAAUAGCUGGAUACACAUGGAGCUGUUUGGGAAUUUUCCUUGCUGCUACCGCGCUGCCACCAAAUGGAAUUGACCAGCGGCUGUUACACUGUUCUUUGCCACUGUGCCUAUGCUCAGAAUAUGCUCACUGCUAAGCUACAAACUCGGACAGGGUCAGAAACAGAGGUGUCCCAUCCCAUUGCAGCCUCCACCACCUGUAACCCCUUCCUGGCAUUGGCCACUGAAGGGUACAAAGGCAAAAGGACCACAGCACCACUUAGGUGUAGCAUGGAUUUUAAACUGCAGUCAGUAUCAGAUCCUGUUUGAUAAAUAAGCUGACUGUUCUCUCUUGAGAACCUGUGGCCUCAACCAGCCACCAAGCUGAUGUGGCCCAAGUCCAUCUCUUGGUCUUCUCCUUUGAAGCACAGCCUAUUUCUGAGCCAAGGGUUGGGGAAGCCUGUCUAGAUGUGGGACUCAUUGCCCCAAACCAGGGAGAGGAAGAGCUCCCACAGGGAGAGCCCAGGCUCUCUUUGCAGCCUUUCCCAGUUUGGUGUUUAAGCAGUGCCAUGUUCCUUGUUUGACAACAAGACAGUCUGUAAAGUAUUGCUCUUAAAAACAAUUAAAAAGAACCCUUUCAUAUUGGCACCAUUGCCUUAGUCCUCUGUGGGUUGGUCUUCAGCCAGCAUUCUGGUGGGAGUGACUGGCAUUAACAAGACUGGAAAUCGGGGGUCAAAGUAAAAUAUCUUUGUUUUGCUUUCAUUCACAAAGUAAUGAAGCCAGCUGCCAAUUACAUCCUCCCAACAGCACUUUGGUCUGUGGACUGCUGUGUGAAUAUUCAGAAGGGAAGUAAGUAUUCAGGGGGUAAACAGGUCUCCCAGCAUUCUGAGUGUUCCAAACCAGUAAUCCACAUGCCAAUUCAAAUAGAACAGCCCCUUGCUAGAUAUUACCACAGAUAAUGACAGUUACAUGGUAGAACUGCCCAUGCCACAAAUAUUUAUUUGGAAAAGUAGUCAUUAAAUGAACCCACUGCCUUAAAUGUCUUGAAUGUUGCAGUCAAGUGUCUGUCAUGUGUUGAUAUCCACACAGAAUUAGGCCCUAAUGAGAGCCUUAGACCCUCAACCAUGCCCCCUUCGUUGGCAUCACAGGGCCUUAUUUGGAAGAGCGGGCAAAGAGGAUGGAAAUCAUAAAAUAUUUCAUGGGAAUCGAACCUAGGGAUAGUGCUCCACUUCUGACGAUGGAGUGAAGACACUUGGCAGACUUGAGCCAGACACUUCACCUAGUAGUUCCUGAAACUGUGAGCACCACUGCACUAAGCCAGUGCGGAGCUGUUAGGGACGGGCCCAGCUCCUGCACCACGGACACAGAAUGUCUGGAGAGGGCCAGCAGGCCCUCUGAGGGUUCUGGAAUCUGUGCACCUUAUUUGACCACACUCCAAAAUUCUGUUUUUAUUUUAACCCUUGAAUCUGCUUUAUGUACAUAAUCAAAAUAUCUAUAUCUAUAUCUAUAUCUAUAUCUAUAUAUUUUUAAUCAUCUACAUGUAAAUGAAGCAAUAGAAUUCUAACAUAAGGCCAAGAAAUGAGACGAAUGUUUGGGGUUUAUGUUUUUUAAGGUAAAUACGGGUAUUGUUUUUAAUUAUUACCAUGUAUUAAAUUGUGGGCUUUGAAACCUAAUGAAACCUGUUAGCCACUUCUCUGUGCCAUAUACUUCCCAUGUUACCAAAAUACCCCCAACUCUUUAGCCAAAAGAGAACCCUGACCUCCUGAGUUUCCAUGCUCCUUUCUGUACCAGGUUUAAAUGUAGUCUUCUGGAGAAGUAUUUUUGACAUUGAGCUCUGGGACAGGACACCUUGGGUUUGUGGACUGCAGCCCACUAUGAUGUUAUUACUUCUCUGGCCAGGCCUCCAGUGGAAGUGCACAGGCACUCCCAAUGUUGUUAAUGCUCUGUCUUCCAUUUGUUCUGGAAUCCUACGUGUUGGUCUGUGGUUCCAUGCAUUAGCUGUUUGUAAAUAAUGCAUUUGCAUACUGAAAAAGGAAUGCCACCUGCCACAGUUGAUGGUGAGGAAGCUCCUUUGACGUGGUGCAAUUUUGAUGAGAUGUCUCUGGGGACACGAGGAUGCCCUAAUGAUGCUGACUUGUCAUGGUUGCAGCAUUUGAACUUUUGGUGUUAAAAAAAAAAACCUGUAAGUCUGUAACCUGGCAACAUUUUACAACCCUGUAUUUUUAAAGAUGGCUUUCUAAUAAAAAAUCCAGAACCACACAGCCCUAUGGUCAAACAAUCCUACGUUUGUGCCUCUGCUUUUAAAGGUGCUGUGCUGGACAGUUGGCAUGCCAGGGUUCGAGAAGAGUGAAUGGCUUGACGUACUUGCAGUUAACUGUGCAAAAUUGGCUGGCUGCCUCUGUUCCUACUGUACUGUAACUUUGAUCAUGUCUGUUCCUGUUCCAUUCUCCCAGGAGCUUCUCUGCAGACUGACACACCCUCCCCCACCCCGGGUAGUGGAGAUGCUGGUGUCUGGGUAGUCAUGGAUUUCUGCUGGACAUUUGAAUGUGAUAAACAAUCCAGCAUUACUUAGGAAAUGCUACAUGCGGAAUGUGCACGUUUCCAGGGGCGAGUAUUGUCAAUCAAAAGGUUUGCAAUGAUUUCCUUCCUGCCAAAAAUAAACAUGUGAAACUGCA